AGCCUGAGUGCUGGCUGAACUGAGAGGAACAGGGUUGGUGCCUGGCACUGGUGUUGCUCCAUUCAUCUCUGAGGUCUCACAGCCCCAGCAUGAGUCCAUCAGCAAAGAAGAGGCCCAAGAACAGCAGGGUUUCCAAGGUCAGACUUGGGACUAGACCCUGGGGAUGCAAGAUGAGAAACUGCGGGACGAGACAGAGCAGCCUGUGAGCAAAGUAAUUGAGCGGAACCGUCUGAGAACGGUGUUAAAAAACUUGUCGCUCUUGAAGCUACUCAAGAGCUCAAACCGCCGGAUCCAAGAACUGCAUAAGCUGGCCAAAAGGUGUUGGCAUUCACUGCUCAGUGUUCCAAAGAUUCUCCGCAUCUCCUCUGGGGAAAACAGUGCCUGCAAUAAAACAAAACAAAAUAAUGAAGAGUUCCAGGAGAUCGGGUGCUCCGAGAAGGAACUCAAGUCCAAGAAAUUAGAGUCCACAGGGGACCCUAAGAAAAAAGAGUACAAGGAGUGGAAGUCCCAGGUGCAGUCAGGGAUGAGGAACAAGGAGAAAACGUCAUUGGCGGCAAUGCCACGGAAAGAAAAGCAUAUAGAGCCUGAGGUUCCAAGGACAUCGAGGGAUGAUAGCUUGAACCCUGGAGUCCAGGGGAGGCAACCACUCACCGAGGGCCCCCGAGUCAUCUUCAUUAAGCCCUACCGCAAUAGAACUCCCAUGGGGCACAUGAAGCAGCUGGAUGUAGCCGACCAGUGGAUCUGGUUUGAGGGGCUGCCCACACGAAUCCACCUCCCGGCGCCCAGGGUGAUGUGCAGAUCCUCCACCCUGCGUUGGGUCAAGCGCCGCUGCACCCGCUUCUGCUCCGCAUCACUUGAAAUGCCUAUGUGGCAUCCAUACAAGGUUGAUGUGACCUGGACGAGAGCCAGAGGUGCGAGCAGAGGGUGGAGAUCGCGCCAUCAGCUGAAGGGGAGGAAUGGGUGGCGAAAUUCACGAGUCUACAAAUAAGAUCUUCCAUAUGGCACCUAAGACGAAUACUGCUUACUCUGCCUGUUUGUCUGGGGCUGGGAAGGAUGAAGGAAAGAGGCCUUCGGUAGAGGGAGCCUGUGUCGCGACUUCAGGCUUCCCCCACCCCCACCCCGAGGCCCCUAAGGUCAGUCUAGAACCAAAGAAGCCAGCGAGCAGCACCCCUCCCCCACCUCCGCGAGCUAGUCUCCUGAGUGGCGCGCUCUGUGAAGUCAGGGCGCUCGUGUGCUUCCUGGGUGCAAAGUGCCUCACAAUCGCCCCGCGAGCUCGCAAGAGGAAACCGCGGCGCGGAGGCAGCAAGUAACUUGCCCAGGCUCACUCAGCUAGAAAGUGGCAGGAGCAAGGGCUCCUGGUUGCUCCCCAUUCCAUUUUCCCAAGAAAGGGAAAAGGCGAAAUGAGAGCCUGCUCAGAAGUCACGAGGCAGGCGGAAUAGCCCCAGCACCCUGUAGGUCAUGCGCGUGCAUUGCGACCUGAUUGUCAAAAAUUGAUUGUCAAAAACUGAUUGCACUGUGGCUGGUGUCAAAAAGUGGAUGUCAGCUGGGCCUCCAAAUGUGUCCUGCCUUGGUCACAGAUCACAGAAGGCACCGGAUCAGGAGGGGGAGCUGGUACUGCAUCUCUACUGCUCCAGGGUGACAUGGCAGGUCCACCCUCAAUCUGAAGACCUCAACCCCAAGCCCUGGUCGACCCCAUCUGGCCGGGGUCACCCUCUGUCGGUAGGAGUCACAGGGUCCUAACCAUGCCGUUGGGGAGAGGAAAGCCAAGGGAGCCCGAGUUUUCUCCGGACGAAGACCUCCAUAUUCCCCAGAGGCAGGCUGCAUGGAGUGGGCGCCCUCGGGAGAGCAGUGGAGCCAUCGAGGGGCACAGAGCUCUCCGGGAUUGGGGGUCAGGGCAGCGAUGCAGAUAGAUCUCCAGUUUGGGACAGAGGGAGAACGAUUGGAUGGACUCUCCCCCCCUCCCACCCCGCCCACUCACACACUCCUCCCCACCAUUACUGGGCACCAAGACUGGGCAUCAGCUGCCGCGCGGACCAGCCUGGGCGGAGCCACAGCGCGGGGACUGCUUAGCACCUCAUAGUGGCUGCUGCGUGCUCCCGAGCUCCUGCUCCCAGCGCAAUCUUCCUGGAGCUCCCCUACGGUCGGUGCCUACCUCCGCCCCCACCACCCCGCUAAUUCCCGUGCAAAUUCCACCCCAGUAACCACUUUCAGCGGUCUUCCCACCCAGCUUGCACUCCAGCCCAUUUCCUGAACAGUCUCCCUUGCAGUUCCCUUGCUGGGUAUUUUCAAUCCCAUCAACUUUCGAAAAUAAUCUCUACUCACUCUUCCAUUCCAUCAA